AGUCUGCAUCUGAGUAACAUGGCGGCGGCGGCGGUAGCCAGGCUGUGGUGGCGCGGGAUCUUGGGGGCCUCGGCGCUGACCAGGGGGACUGGGCGACCCUCCGUUCUGUUGCUGCCGGUGAGGCGGGAGAGCGCCGGGGCCGACACGCGCCCCACUGUCAGACCACGGAAUGAUGUGGCCCACAAGCAGCUCUCAGCUUUUGGAGAGUAUGUGGCUGAAAUCUUGCCCAAGUAUGUCCAACAAGUUCAGGUGUCCUGCUUCAAUGAGUUAGAGGUCUGUAUCCAUCCUGAUGGCGUCAUCCCAGUGCUGACUUUCCUCAGGGAUCACACCAAUGCACAGUUCAAAUCUCUGGUUGACUUGACAGCAGUGGACGUCCCAACUCGGCAAAACCGUUUUGAGAUUGUCUACAACCUGUUGUCUCUGCGCUUCAACUCACGGAUCCGUGUGAAGACCUACACAGAUGAGCUGACGCCCAUUGAGUCUGCUGUCUCUGUGUUCAAGGCAGCCAACUGGUAUGAAAGGGAGAUCUGGGACAUGUUUGGAGUCUUCUUUGCUAACCACCCUGAUCUAAGAAGGAUCCUGACAGAUUAUGGCUUCGAGGGACAUCCUUUCCGGAAAGACUUUCCUCUAUCUGGCUAUGUUGAGUUACGUUAUGAUGAUGAAGUGAAGCGGGUGGUGGCAGAGCCGGUGGAGUUGGCCCAAGAGUUCCGCAAAUUUGACCUGAACAGCCCCUGGGAGGCUUUCCCAGUCUAUCGCCAACCCCCGGAGAGUCUCAAGCUUGAAGCCGGAGACAAGAAGCCUGAUGCCAAGUAGCUCCAGGGAACGCAUGUGGAUCCUAGACAGCGCCUUAUCUAUGAUUGAGUGUCCGUGUAAAUAAAUUCCUACUUAGACUUA